GGAAGUGGUGCCCAGUCGGGACCCGUAGGGAGAGGCGGGUUGCGGGCGGCGGCGGCGGCGGCGGCGGCGGUGGUGGUUGUGGCGAGGCUGUGCGGCAGGGCGCACGGGACCUGUGCUGCAGCGGCUCUCUCAGGCCGUGGGUCGUCGCUGCAGCUGCCGGGAAAGAAGGAAACGACGACUCCGGGGGCGAACUUGGCACACAGGGAGGAAGGGAAAGGGUGUGUGAGGAGGGCUGUGGGUAUAUUUGGCAUCAGGGAGAAGGACCUCAAAACUUGUUUUUCAUAUAGUACUAGCUGAUCGUCGGGUUUUUUUUUGUUUUGGUUUGGUUUUUUUUUUUUUGGAUGACAGAUUCUGGAGACACCUGGCAUCUCCGUUUUUGAGUUUCUCCCCGCUCUUGUCAGUUGAUUCGUAGGCCUGAAAUGCAUGGUCAUGGAGGCUAUGAUUCUGAUUUUAGUGAUGAUGAACGCUGUGGAGAAUCCAGCAAAAGGAAAAAAAGGACAGUUGAAGAUGACUUACUGCUCCAAAAACCAUUUCAGAAAGAAAAACAUGGAAAGGUGGCCCAUAAACAAGUUGCAGCAGAAUUGCUGGAUAGGGAAGAAGCAAGAAAUAGAAGGUUUCAUCUCAUAGCUAUGGAUGCUUAUCAAAGACAUACAAAGUUCGUAAAUGACUAUAUUUUAUACUAUGGUGGCAAAAAAGAAGACUUCAAGCGUUUGGGGGAAAAUGACAAGACAGACUUGGAUGUUAUACGAGAAAAUCAUAGAUUCCUAUGGAAUGAGGAGGACGAAAUGGACAUGACUUGGGAGAAGAGACUUGCUAAGAAAUACUAUGAUAAAUUAUUUAAGGAAUACUGCAUAGCAGAUCUCAGUAAAUAUAAAGAAAAUAAGUUUGGAUUUAGGUGGCGAGUAGAAAAAGAAGUAAUUUCAGGAAAAGGUCAAUUUUUCUGUGGAAAUAAAUAUUGUGAUAAAAAAGAAGGCUUAAAGAGUUGGGAAGUUAAUUUUGGUUAUAUUGAGCAUGGUGAGAAGAGAAAUGCACUUGUUAAAUUAAGGUUAUGCCAAGAAUGUUCCAUUAAAUUAAAUUUCCAUCACAGGAGAAAAGAAAUCAAGUCAAAAAAAAGAAAAGAUAAAACCAAAAAAGACUGUGAAGAGUCAUCACAUAAAAAAUCCAGAUUAUCUUCUGCAGAAGAGGCCUCCAAGAAAAAAGAUAAAGGACAUUCAUCUUCAAAGAAAUCUGAAGAUUCUCUACUUAGAAACUCUGAUGAGGAAGAAAGUGCUUCAGAAUCUGAACUUUGGAAGGGUCCACUACCAGAGACAGAUGAAAAAUCACAGGAAGAAGAAUUUGAUGAGUAUUUUCAGGAUUUGUUUCUAUGAGACGAGAGAGAGAAGCCUCCGCUCCUUAAUGUGAAACUUCAUGAAGUUUUAAACUUCAUGCAAUUUGAAAUUCCAUAUAAGUUUUUAUCUGCAAGUUACAGCUUGUGUGGUUUGUCUUUGGAAAUAAAAAUCCAGGUUCUCUCAGAAUGUCAGAGGCUUUGGAAGUUCAUUAGUUCAAUUAAAGACUUUCCUGUCCUUUAAAUAUCUUUUCAAUUGCUUAUCUACAAUUCUGUUUUAUUUGUAGCUCCUAGAGGAUAGAGCUGGACAGAUUCCAUUGUUCCUACAUUUUGUAGGUUUUUUUUCACUGCCUUCAUUAUGUAUCUUCUCUUGCCUUCAUUAUUUUAUUUUAUUAUUUCUUCUUUUUCUCUUUUUUAGAGCCACCAAUACUGGAUUUGUUUGUUUUUCAUUUUUUUCUUUUGUGGAAACGGAGUCCUCCUGUGUUGCCCAGGCUGGUAUUCAAACUCCUGGCCUUAUGCAUUCCUCCCACCCUGGCCUCCCAGAGUGCUGGGAUUACAGGUGUGAGCCACCAUGCUCUGCCAAUUAUUUUAAAUUACUAGGAUUAAAGUAUAUUAUGUAUGUCUUUAACUUCUUUCUUUCCCAUUGAUAAACUGGCACCCUUCUUUUAAGUACCUGCUCUCCCAUUACCACCUAUUUCCAGCUGCUUUUUGAGGUUUUUUGCUUGCCUGUCUCUUGCUUCCUUCUUAACCUCUACCACUUAAGAGAGUUUGUUAUAAUCAAAUUUGACUUCCUAGCCUGUGGAUAAUUUACUAUUAAGUAAAUUAUUACCACAGGGAGCCAGUGAGGUCCCAGUAGUCUAAAACAGUUCAUGUGUUCACAAAAAUUGCCUCCCCGGCAGAGAUUAUGCAGUAAGAUAAUUUAACUGAAUAAUACUAUGUGCAUGUAUCUUGCCUCAGAUAUACUCAUGCAAAUAUGAAUAUACCUCUGAUAUGGUUUGGCUCUGUGUCCCCACCCAAAUCUCAUCUUGAAUGUGUACUCCCAUAAUUCCCACAUUUUAUAGGAGGGAUCCAGUGAGAGAUAAUUUGAAUCAAGGGGGCGGUUUCCCCCAUAUUGUUCUUGUGGUAGUGAAUAAGUCUCACAAGAUCUGAUGGUUUUAUCAGGGGCUUCUGCUUUUGCAUCCUUCUCAUUUUCUUUUGCUGCUGCCAUGUAAGAAGUGCCUUUUGCCUCCCACCAUGAUUCUGAGGCUUUCCCAGCCAUGUGGAACUGUAAGUCCAAUUAAACCUCUUUUUCUUCCCCAGUCUCUGGUAUGUCUUUAUCAGCAGUGUGAAAAUGGACUAAUAGAACUUCUAUGCAGAAAUAUAAAAUGUAACUUCUUAACAUAAGGUCCUAGUCGCAAGGGUCUAUGGAGGUGCUUCAGGAGAUCCAAGCCUUUUUAGAAUCUGUGCAAACUUCUGUGUAUGUUUUUUGGAGGAAAAGUCCAUAAAUUUCAAAUUUUCAAAAAUCAGAUUUUCAAAAGGAUUUAUUGAUUUCUGAAAACUAGCAAAGAUCUGCUUUUAUAAAGAGCAAAUAGAUGGAUAGAUAUAGGAGAAGAUGCUUGACUUGAUGAAUAAGAGAAAGGACAUAUAGAAAAUGAACUGAACAUAAGCAAGUAUUUUAUUGAAGAUAUACUAUUUUAAAUAACAUUUAAACACGGAAUGAUUGGCAAUAAACUGCAAAAUGAGUAAUUUGGUAUCAUUUUAAAAUGGUUAUUAUCAGAGAUUUUCCUUUUAUUAAACAGUUAUUCAUUAAUUCCACAAAUAUUUAUCAGGCUUCUAUUAUAUGUGAGGCACUGAGCUGGGCAUGGCUGUAAAGGAACCAUCUAGGAAGUAAUUAUGCAAUCAUUUCUGAACCUGUUUCAGAAAAGUAAAUCAGUGUUGGGUUUAUCAGUGUUUAACAUUGUUUGAUAGUCCCCUCACUUCUUGAAUAAAUUGUUUUUUUUCACCUCA